GGGCUCAGAGAACUCCACACCUGCACACCUCCCUCUCACCUGCUCCUCUACCUGCUCCACCCUCAACCCACCAGAACCAUGGGCUGCUCUGGCUGCUCUGGAGGCUGUGGCUCCAGCUGUGGGGGCUGUGGCUCCAGCUGUGGGGGCUGUGGCUCCGGCUAUGGGGGCUGUGGCUCCGGCUGCUGUGUACCUGUCUGCUGCUGCAAGCCCGUGUGCUGCUGUGUGCCAGCCUGUUCCUGCUCCAGCUGUGGCUCCUGUGGGGGCUCCAAGGGGGUCUGUGGCUCUUGUGGGGGCUGCAAGGGGGGCUGUGGCUCCUGUGGAGGCUCCAAGGGGGGCUGUGGCUCCAGCUGCUGUGUGCCCGUCUGCUGCUCCUCCAGCUGUGGCUCCUGUGGGGGUUCCAAGGGGGUCUGUGGAUUUCGUGGGGGCUCCAAGGGGGGCUGCGGUUCUUGUGGCUGCUCCCAGUGCAGCUGCUAUAAGCCCUGCUGCUGCUCCUCAGGCUGUGGGUCAUCCUGCUGCCAGUCCAGCUGCUGCAAGCCCAGCUGCUCCCAGUCCAGCUGCUGUAAGCCCUGCUGUUCCCAGUCCAGCUGCUGUAAGCCCUGCUGCUGCUCCUCAGGCUGUGGGUCAUCCUGCUGCCAGUCCAGCUGCUGCAAACCCUGCUGUUCCCAGUCCAGCUGCUGUAAGCCCUGCUGCUGCUCCUCAGGCUGUGGGUCAUCCUGCUGCCAGUCCAGCUGCUGCAAGCCCUGCUCCUCCCAGUCCAGCUGCUGUGUCCCAAUUUGCUGCCAGUGCAAGAUCUGAGGCUCUGCCCACAAACCUCAGUGGGUCCUACAGAUCCGGGCUCUCCAGGAAUGAUUGCAGCUGUGUCCUGAAUUCCUGAAGCACGUCUCUGAAUCUGUCCUCCU